GGAGCUGGGGGGAGGGGAUGGCGUGGGAAGGAGAGGGUUAAAGGUGGGGCCGGCCCUACAAACGCGCGCACACACUCCUUACUCAGACCCAGUCACUCGCGUUUCCCUGGCACUUAGAUGGGCCUGUGGGUGGCGGAGGGGGGGGGGUGGAUUGAAUUGGAGCCUGCGCCGGAGCCCUUUGCACCCCAAGCUCCUGCAGCCCGACCUGGGGGCCCCGCUGUCUGAACUCACAGCUCCCUGCCGAGCCCCCUCUCCGGGGUGCACAUAACGCUCCAGCGCGCGCACACACCUCGGACAGUCCCCUCGCGUCUCACGUGACACGCGGCCCGGACGUGCCACCCUGCCCACGCGCUCACGCACGCGUGCACACACCAGCCUCCUGGUCGCUGCCCCACUCCGUCCCGACGCCCCUGCGACCCCGAAGGCACUCAUUGACUGACACACCUACACUCAUUCACAGACGCACACUCCCCCCAUACGCCAACCCCAGACACACAUUCAUAACCAGGCCCGAGAGAAGUACACACGCACCCCCUCACUGCCUACUCCUGCUUUCGGGAGCCUGAGUCAUUCCUGCCCCCUCGUAGGGUUCCCCAUUUCCCGGUGCGCGGGCACCCUGAGACAGCCUUGGGAAUUCGUUCGCGUCCCCUUCCACCUGGGUCCCCUUCCCCAGUUUGCGCCCCGUAACACUCAGCCAAGGACUUCCUGUGGGUCCCAGGUCAGGGGCCAAGGGGUCCUGGACCGCUGCCACAGCCCCGGUGCGCCCGGGGGAGGCGCUUCCUUUUCCUGAACUCUGGGAUCCUGCGGGAGGAAGUGGGGAAGUUGGGCGGGGGUGCAGCCGAGGGCGUGCCGACUGUGGAGGGGCCGACCCUCGCGCAGCUCUGGGCCUUCCUUGGGGAGGAGCUGGGGUGCCAGAGGCCCAGGCUGAGGAGCUUGGCGGCGAGGAGGCCCCGUGUGGGCCGCGGCCCGGCCCUCACCAUGGAGUCCAUGUUCGAGGACGACAUCAGCAUCCUGACGCAGGAGGCCCUGGGGCCUAGUGAGGUGUGGCUGGACAGUCCCGGAGACCCCUCGCUUGGGGGCGACAUGUGCUCCGCCUCCCACUUUGCCCUCAUCACUGCUUACGGAGACAUCAAGGAACGGCUGGGGGGCCUGGAGAGGGAGAACGCCACCCUCCGACGCCGCCUCAAAGUCUACGAGAUCAAGUACCCACUGAUCAGUGACUUUGGAGAGGAGCAUGGCUUUUCUCUGUAUGAAAUCAAGGAUGGCUCCCUGCUGGAGGUGGAGAAGGUCAGCCUGCAGCAACGGCUCAACCAGUUCCAGCAUGAGUUACAGAAGAACAAGGAGCAGGAAGAACAGCUUGGAGAGAUGAUCCAGGCCUACGAGAAACUCUGCGUGGAGAAGAGUGACUUGGAGACAGAGCUGAGGGAGAUGAGGGCCCUGGUGGAGACGCACCUGCGUCAGAUCUGUGGUUUGGAGCAGCAGCUGCGGCAACAGCAAGGCCUCCAGGAUGCAGCCUUCUCCAACCUGAGCCCACCGCCAGCCCCCGCCCCUCCCUGCACUGAUUUAGACCUGCACUACCUGGCACUGAGAGGGGGAUCUGGCUUGAGUCAUGCAGGCUGGCCGGGCUCCACACCCAGUGUGAGUGACCUGGAGCGGCGGCGGCUAGAAGAGGCUUUGGAGGCCGCGCAGGGAGAGGCCCGGGGGGCUCAGCUCCGGGAGGAGCAGCUCCAGGCCGAGUGCGAGCGGCUGCAGGGGGAGCUGAAGCAGCUGCAGGAGACCCGGGCCCAGGAUCUGGCCUCCAACCAGUCGGAGCGAGACAUGGCGUGGGUGAAAAGAGUUGGGGAUGAUCAGGUGAAUUUGGCGCUGGCCUACACCGAGCUGACGGAGGAGCUGGGCCGGCUUCGGGAGUUGAGUUCCCUACAGGGGAGAAUCUUGAGGACUCUGUUGCAGGAACAGGCCCGGAGUGGCGGCCAGAGGCACUCGCCGCUGUCACAACGCCACUCCCCGGCCCCCCAGUGCCCCUCCCCCUCCCCGCCUGCCCGAGCGGCUCCCCCGUGCCCCCCGUGCCAGUCCCCCGUCCCCCAGCGCCGCUCUCCCGUGCCCCCGUGCCCCUCGCCGCAGCAGCGCCGCUCUCCGGCCUCACCCUCCUGCCCGUCGCCCGUCCCGCAGCGCCGCUCGCCGGUGCCGCCGUCGUGCCAGUCCCCCAGCCCGCAGCGCCGUUCCCCGGUGCCCCCCAGCUGCCCGGCCCCGCAGCCCCGGCCACCGCCGCCGCCCCCGCCGGGCGAGAGGACGCUGGCCGAGCGCGCCUACGCCAAGCCGCCCAGCCACCACGUGAAGGCCGGCUUCCAGGGCCGCCGCAGCUACUCUGAGCUGGCGGAGGGCGCGGCCUACGCGGGCGCCUCCCCGCCCUGGCUGCAGGCCGAAGCGGCCACUCUCCCCAAGCCCCGGGCCUACGGCAGCGAGCUCUACGGCCCUGGCAGGCCCCUCAGCCCGCGGCGCGCCUUCGAGGGCAUCCGGCUGCGCUUCGAGAAGCAGCCGUCGGAGGAGGACGAGUGGGCUGUGCCCACCAGCCCGCCCAGCCCGGAGGUGGGCACCAUCCGCUGCGCCUCCUUCUGCGCGGGCUUCCCCAUCCCCGAGUCGCCCGCCGCCACCGCCUACGCCCACGCCGAGCACGCGCAGUCCUGGCCGUCCAUCAACUUGCUGAUGGAGACGGUGGGCUCCGACAUCCGCAGCUGCCCCCUCUGCCAGCUGGGUUUCCCUGUCGGGUACCCGGAUGAUGCCCUCAUCAAACACAUUGACUCCCACCUGGAGAACAGCAAGAUCUAGGGCACCAGCCCCACCCACUGGCUGUUUCUCCGUCCUCUCCUAUCACCCCCAAACACUCACUUUGAAUGCUGCAUGAAUCUCGUGGGGGGUCCCUGCCCUUGCGACCCCCAGAUACCUCCACUUGCUACCGAGUCAACGUGUGUGCCAUCUUCCCUGGUCCAGGCACCACUCAGCUCUGGCUCUUCCUGGGAGGUCAGCCGAGGCUCCCCCCAUGCUCCUGGUUUCUGCUUAGGAGGUGGGGACUUGGGCUGGGAUGGGGACGGCAUACCCCUCCCAGGCCUCUCCCUCUGCCUUUCUGUUCUUAAUCAGGGUUGGAUCCAAGAAGGUGUCCAGUGCUUGGGCCUGGGGUGGGGGGAAGGUGUUAGAGGACUCCAGGAGCUCCUGCACCCCUCCCCAAAUGUCCAUCUUUCUCAGACGGGGCUCUGUCUGGGGAGCACCCACAGGCUGCCUUUGGGGUCCCAGAGCCUGCUCUGUGCACUGACCCCAGUUCCUCCAUCCUGUGGCCAGCCUAGGGCUCAUGGCAUGGGCCCCCACUGGGGGAGGGAGGCAUCUUGUUUCUUGUGGUUCCCUGCAGGCCAGUCCUGUCCUCCUUUCCCUGUUCUGCCCACUCUGGGGAAUAGGGAGGGGAGGAGAGGAGAGGAGAGGGAGGAUCCUGGAGGACUGGGAAGAUCUAGCCUAAAGAGGCUUCUCUGAGGGCCAGGGCCCUACAGCAUGCCCCUACGGCCAGGGGACUGUCUGCCAGCCUCCCAGGCCCAUGCCCUCCUGGUGCCCCUGGCACUGAGGCACAGAUCGUCAAGGCAGGUACCCCCUCAACCCUUCUUCCACUGGAGCCCCUGACACCACAGGUGCCCUGGAGCCCUUGUGUGACUCAGCCUCUGUUAGCUGGGUGGGUGUCAUCAGCCCCUGCCUCCCAGGCCAGAACCUGAGAACGGGCCCAGGGUGCUGUGGAGAUCAACUUCAAAAGAGCUAACCCCUUCCCACACUCCACCCACCCACCUACAUUUCCUCUGUGAAAUCUACCUCAGAGUUGUACCCUCAGAAGGACGGGUAAGCAGGAGGCCAGGGGGUCCCCAGGGCUGAGGUGGGGAGCCUUCUACGGCGAAAGCCUGCCACCCCACAAUGAAUCCACCCUGCUCCACUGCGCGCCUCUCCCAGGUCUCAGCUCUGGGUGGGGAGCAGUGGCCGCUACCGACAGCGCAUGUCCCGCUCUUAUCCAACUCUUCCAGGCCCCACCUCCCUGCACCCCUCCCCUCUAUAGAGCAGGGGAGUGAAGGGGUAUGUCAGGCGGGGAAGGGGCCAAGGACACGUCAUUGUACCCUGAGCGUCCCCAGGGAGUGGAAAUGGGGAAGGGGGCCUGGAGAGGGGAGGCAGGGGCCCCUGUGCUCUCUGAACAAGUUGAAAGUCCAAAUAAAACUUACCUGUUCCAUCUGUGCUCAA